GACCCCGCCUCAGUCUUCCAGGGCGGCGGUGGGUGUCCGCUUCUCUCUGCUCUUCGACUGCACCGCACUCGCGCGUGACCCUGACUCCCCCUAGUCAGCUCAGCGGUGCUGCCAUGGCGUGGCGGCGGCGCGAAGCCAGCGUCGGGGCUCGCGGCGUGUUGGCUCUGGCGUUGCUCGCCCUGGCCCUGUGCGUGCCCGGGGCCCGGGGCCGGGCUCUCGAGUGGUUCUCGGCCGUGGUAAACAUCGAGUACGUGGACCCGCAGACCAACCUGACGGUGUGGAGCGUCUCGGAGAGUGGCCGCUUCGGCGACAGCUCGCCCAAGGAGGGCGCGCAUGGCCUGGUGGGCGUCCCGUGGGCGCCCGGCGGAGACCUCGAGGGCUGCGCGCCCGACACGCGCUUCUUCGUGCCCGAGCCCGGCGGCCGAGGGGCCGCGCCCUGGGUCGCCCUGGUGGCUCGUGGGGGCUGCACCUUCAAGGACAAGGUGCUGGUGGCGGCGCGGAGGAACGCCUCGGCCGUCGUCCUCUACAAUGAGGAGCGCUACGGGAACAUCACCUUGCCCAUGUCUCACGCGGGAACAGGAAAUAUAGUGGUCAUUAUGAUUAGCUAUCCAAAAGGAAGAGAAAUUUUGGAGCUGGUGCAAAAAGGAAUUCCAGUAACGAUGACCAUAGGGGUUGGCACCCGGCAUGUACAGGAGUUCAUCAGCGGUCAGUCUGUGGUGUUUGUGGCCAUUGCCUUCAUCACCAUGAUGAUUAUCUCGUUAGCCUGGCUAAUAUUUUACUAUAUACAGCGUUUCCUAUAUACUGGCUCUCAGAUUGGAAGUCAGAGCCAUAGAAAAGAAACUAAGAAAGUUAUUGGCCAGCUUCUACUUCAUACUGUAAAGCAUGGAGAAAAGGGAAUUGAUGUUGAUGCUGAAAAUUGUGCAGUGUGUAUUGAAAAUUUCAAAGUAAAGGAUAUUAUUAGAAUUCUGCCAUGCAAGCAUAUUUUUCAUAGAAUAUGCAUUGACCCAUGGCUUUUGGAUCACCGAACAUGUCCAAUGUGUAAACUUGAUGUCAUCAAAGCCCUAGGAUAUUGGGGAGAGCCUGGGGAUGUACAGGAGAUGCCUGCUCCAGAAUCUCCUCCUGGAAGGGAUCCAGCUGCAAAUUUGAGUCUAGCUUUACCAGAUGAUGACGGAAGUGAUGACAGCAGUCCACCAUCAGCCUCCCCUGCUGAAUCUGAGCCACAGUGUGAUCCCAGCUUUAAAGGAGAUGCAGGAGAAAAUACGGCAUUGCUAGGUGAGCGGUGUGCAAAUUAUAAAACAAUAGAAUGUGGCCAGGAGUGGUGGCUCACACCUGUAAUCUCAGUGCUUUGGGAGUUUAAGGUGGGAGGAUUGCUCGAGUUUGAGCUAUCGAAGAGUAAGUAACCAGAAAUUUGAGAACAGCCUGGGCAGCAUAGUGAGACCCCAUCUCUACAAAAACUUCACAGAUUAGCCAGGUAUGGUGGCAUUCUCCUGUAGUCCCAGCUACUCAGAAUGCUGAGGCAGGAGAGUGGCUUGUGACCAAGAGUUCAGGCUGCAGUGAGCUAUGAUCCUGUCACUGUACUCCAGCCUGAGCCUGGGUGACAGAGCAAGACCCUGUCUCUUAAAAAAAAAAAAAAAAAAAAAAGGAAUUUUAUUAGUAGCUGUGAAAGAAAAUAAAGAAAUACAUAAAGUGCAGAAAAGCAUAAGGAAAAAAUGAAAAUAGUCGUCCCCCACGUAGAGAUGUCAUCUUAACACUUUGAUAAUUACCUUUCCAGAUGUUUUUCUGGAAAUCGAAAGGUGUUUAAGGGUCGGUGAAUAUCACUUAUGGGCUGUUAGGUAACCUACUUUUUACUUAAUAUAUGAAGCUCUUUCUAUGUUGAUAAAUAGAUAAUUUUUUACAGCUACAGAGUAUUACAUUUUGAAUUUUCUAUAAUUUCUUGAAACUAAUUAAUGAGUGUUUGUAUUAUCAGUAGCACUUUGAAAUCAUUAUGUAUAUAUACUUAUGCCUUGUCUAAUUGUUUUCUGUCACUCUGAUAGGUAAAAUGUAGUGAACUGCAUGUUUUUUGUUUUGUUUUGUUUUUUGUGUUUUAUUUUGGUUUUUGAGACAGGGUCUUGCUCUGUCACCCUGGCUGGAGUGUAGUGAUGAGAACACAGCUCACUGCAGCCUCAAACUCCUGGGCUUAACCAAUCCUGCCACCUCUGCCUCCCAAGUAGCUGAGACCACAGGCGUGUGCCACCACAUCUAGCUAACUUUUUAAAUUUUUUUGAAGUGAUGAAGUCUCACCAUGUUGUCUAGACUCAUUGCAUUUUUUAAAUUACAUUUUUGUCCUCUUUUCACAUUGUUGGUCAUCUUUAUUCUUUGAUGAACUGCUUAUUUUAUCCCUAGCUUAUUUUUUUAUGGAGAUAGUAAUUUUUUCAUAUUGAUCCUUAGAGCUUUUUAUACAUUGAAAAUACUAGGGCUUUGUCAUAUAUUUUAUGUAUUUCUCCCCCAAUUUCUGUAUCCUUUGGCUUUUCAUUGUACUUUCCAGAUAGAAAUUAUGUAGUUUAGUUUCCCGUUCUCUCAUGAUUCUGCCUUUGAUUGCAUGCUGACUUAGGAAGGUCUUUCUUAUGUUAGGAUUGUAAAGAUAUUGACCUGUACUUUGCUAGUAUUUGUGGGUUUUGUAUUUUACAUUUAAAUCUUAAUGUAAGAUUUAAAUGUAAAUCUUAAACAUCUUAAACACAUAUAGUUUAAGGUGUGAGGGGAGAUUUAACUAAUCUGUUUUUUCCUUUUAUUCCACUUAUUAAACCCAAAUGUUUAAUCAGUUGUCCUAAUAUUGUUUAGUGAAUAAUAAUUGCAAAUAAUAUGUUUUUAUAUUUGCAAGGCAAUUUCCUUCAUCUUUAUUCUUCUUUUAAAAAAUUUCUGGACUAUUCUACAUUAUCAUCAUCAUCAUCAUUAUUAUUAUUAUUAUUAUUAUUAUUUGAGAUGGAGUCUUGCUCUGUCGGCCAGUCUGGAGUGCAGUGACACGAUCUCAGCUCACUGCAGCCUCUGCCUCCUGGGUUCAAGUGAUUUGCCCACCUCAGGUGAUCCACCCUCCUGGGACUCCCAAAGUGCUGGGAUUACAGGCAUGAGCCACCACACCCAGCCUAUUCUACAUUUUUUAAAGAUUAAUUCUAAAAUCAUUUUGCCAAGUAAAAGAAAAUCUCAUCAGAAUUUUUAUUGGAAUUGGAUUCACUUAAAGGUUAUUUUAAGUGGGAAGAAUCGAUGCUUCAGGUUUUGAAUUUUGUCAUCCUAGAAGAGGAAGCAUAUUUUUCCAAAGCAGUAAGAUUGAAACUAAGUCAGUUUUUUUGUAGCACAUUUAGGAUCUGUGAGGCAAAAAUCGGUAGAAAUAUUAGAAUGUAAGUAUUAACCAGCACCAGAGGAAGAAAAGACUGCAUUGUGGAACAAAAAAAGGAGAAUAGAUUUCAGAGAAUUAUAAAAUUGUAGCGAUUGAUCUGUGUAGGCAUUCUCCUAACAGCUCUCCAGCUAAGACUGGGCCACCUUGCAAAGCAGCAUGUUCCCUUGGUAAAUGGCUCUUAUUUUUAAGAAUGUCUUUAUAUAGAGCCAGAGUGCAUACCAGUGUGAUUUUGCCAUUGCCUUCCAACUCCAGAAAGAAAACUAACUUUGCCUUCUCUAGUACAUGAGCACCCUGGAGAUACUAAAACUCUUAUUCUGACUAAAUGUCUUUCAAGAGCAGCCUCCAGAUUUUUCUGCAUUCUUGCUACCUUGUUAACUUGCAGUGCCUUACAGUUUACCAUUGGCUGUCCUGAAAUACCCUCUUAGAACUAAGAUAAUACAAUUUGAAAUCAUGGGUAGAAAUCAUGAAAUCAUGGGUAGAAAUAAAGAAGGUGGAAGAAGCAGCUAGGUUUCCAAAGCAGCAAAAUGUCAGAUACAUUCUGAAGCAGCCAGUUUCCCCAGUGUCCCCACCCCACCCCGUAUGGGGCUCACAUUCUAUUUUUCUCUUUGUCCUUUUUUUAAAUUCUCAAGUAUUGUGCAACAGCAAGUUGACUUUAUCUGUUAAUGUUCUUUCAGCCUUAUAACGGUAACGACAUAAAUUGAAAAACACUAAAUUAGAAAAAUCAGGCAUUAAUACUUCCAGAAAAAACUGUGGUUUCACUUAUAGUUGAGAAAACAUUUACUAGACUCUCAGGAGCAACUAGGAAAUGAAUGUGGAAGUUACUCAUGGUAGACCCUGGAGAAGGUGUUUCCCUGUGGAAGUGCACCUUCCACUCUCCAGUUACAUCACUCUCCACCUACUUCACCUCCUUGAAGGGGAGUGCAAAAUAUUUGGUUGGGUGUGGGGGGAAUUGGAGAGAUUGAUCAAAAGGUACAAAGUUUCAGUUAGGAGCAAGUUCAAGAGCUCCAUUGUACAGCAUGGUGACUACAGUUCAUAACAGUGUAUAGUAUUCUUGAAAGAUGCCCAAAGAGUAGAUUUUAAAUGUUCUCACUUCAAAUGAAUAUGUCAGGUAAUGCACAUGAAUUAGUGUGAUUUAGCCAUUCCACAAUGUAUACAUGUUUCAGAACAUCAUGUUGUAUACCAUAUAUAUAUACAGUUUUUGUCAAUUUAAACAGUAAAUACAAAUUUUGUAUUUAUAAAUAUACACUUAUAUUUAUAAAACAAGAGGAAGCAUUUUAUGAGAUUACUUAUGUUAUUUCACCAUUUAAUAGAAACUUCAGGCUGGACAUGGUGGCUCACACUUGUAAUCCUAGCACUUUUGGAGGUAGGGUGGCAGGGAGCAGAUUGCAUCGCAUGAGGCCAGUCUGGGGAACAUGCAGAAACUCUGUCUCUACUUAAAAUUAGCGGGGCGUGGUGGCGUGUGCCUACUGUAGUCCUAGCUCUCUGGGAAGCUGAGGUGGGAGGAUCACUUGAACCCAGGAAGUCGAGGAUGCAGCGAGCCGUGACCAUGAUCAUGUCACUGCACUGCAGCCUGGGUGAGAGAGUGAGACCCUAUAUCAAAAAAGAAAAGAAAAAAGAAACUUUAAAUUGGCAAAAUAAAAAGUAAUGGGAUCUGCUGCUAUCUUUAAGGAAGUAUUCUAUUCUAAGAGCCUUUUGUGUGAAGUGAUUUUGUAUACUUCAUAAUAGCAACUGUCUGGAUUUCAGUACCAGCUCCUCCUCUUCCUUGCCAUCUAUAAACCGGGGCUGGUGACAUGUUAAUCUCUACCUCUUAGGGUCAAUAUAAAUACUGGCUAUUGUUUUCAUUGGUGGCAGCAUCACCAUCACCUUAGCUACUUGUUCAACUUUUGGGAACAUCUUCUGGUACCGCCAUCUCUGACUGUCUUUAAAGACUGAUCUGCUGAUGAGAUUAAUGUUGGCUAGGCUAAUGCUAGAAAACUCCUCAUAUGAUGAAGAUGUUUACCGAUUUUUCUUGUUGGCUAUCAGUGGAAUGGGUUAUCAGUUUUCCAUGUAUGUUUUAUUUAAAAUUUUCUGUUAGCCGGGCGCGGUGGCUCAUGCCUGUAAUCCCAGCAUUUUGGGAGGCUGAGGU